GUGGCUAUAUAAACAUGGCUGGCGUGGCCGCGCGGCGGGGCCGUGCCAAUCGCGCGUAGGGGGCUGUGGGCACUCGGGGUUCGUAGUUUUGAAAUUUCUGGCGGGGGAGCAGCUGCGCAGUUAGGCUCGAGGUGUGAGCGACGACCUUCCGGGAGCCGCAAGUCCAGGCUCCCCCGCAGCGGGACCCGAGCCUGAGGCGCAGGGCUGAGGCAGCGCACGUGUGAGCGCCGCUGAGGAAGCUGCGAGAGGUCGGGCGGGUGUCGCUCCGGGGGCAGCCCAGGCUCGCGCGGACGAGAGGAAGGUCCGGGACGCGCGUGUCCUGCCGUGCAGCGGGCGCCCGUCACUGACUUCGCUGCUGCGGCCCCCGCGCCUCUCCCCAGCGAUGCUGUGGAACCCGAACCGCACCGGAGUCGGCUGCCGCGCGCCAAGCCUCCCCUCACCUCUGCUCCCGGAACCGCAGCGCCAAAGCUGCCGCUGAGCCCCUGGGGGAUGCCCGCCGGCCUCACCGAACCCGCCGGCGCCGCUCCCCCGGCUGCUGUGAGCGCCUCGGGGACCGUGACCAUGGCCCCGGCCGGGGCGCUGCCGGUGCGGGUGGAGAGCACUCCGGUGGCCCUGGGCGCCGUGACUAAGGCUCCUGUCAGCGUCUGCGUGGAGCCCACGGCGUCCCAGCCCCUGCGGUCCCCCGUGGGGACCCUGGUGACCAAAGUGGCUCCGGUCAGCGCCCCUCCUAAAGUCAGCAGCGGCCCUAGGCUGCCUGCUCCUCAGAUAGUCGCCGUGAAAGCCCCCAACACCACGACAAUCCAGUUUCCUGCUAAUUUGCAGCUUCCUCCAGGAACCGUUUUGAUUAAAAGUAACAGUGGUCCGUUGAUGUUGGUAUCUCCUCAGCAAACUGUAACAAGAGCCGAGACCACAAGUAACAUAACCUCAAGGCCAGCAGUACCAGCGAAUCCUCAAACAGUCAAAAUCUGUACAGUGCCGAACUCUAGCUCACAAUUAAUCAAGAAAGUGGCAGUGACACCUGUUAAAAAAUUGGCACAAAUAGGAACUACUGUGGUAACCACUGUUCCGAAGCCUUCCUCAGUACAAUCUGUGGCUGUGCCAACCAGUGUCGUCACAGUUACUCCUGGAAAGCCAUUGAAUACUGUAACUACCCUGAAGCCUUCAAGUUUGGGAGCAUCAUCCACUCCUUCAAAUGAGCCCAAUCUUAAAGCAGAGAACUCAGCAGCUGUUCAGAUUAAUCUUUCUCCGACAAUGCUAGAAAAUGUGAAGAAAUGCAAGAACUUCCUUGCAAUGUUAAUAAAACUAGCAUGUAGUGGAUCACAGUCCCCAGAAAUGGGGCAAAAUGUGAAGAAGCUGGUGGAACAACUUUUGGAUGCAAAAAUCGAAGCAGAAGAAUUUACUAGGAAACUGUAUGUUGAACUCAAGUCUUCACCUCAGCCUCACCUGGUUCCUUUUCUUAAGAAAAGCGUGGUUGCCUUACGACAACUUCUGCCUAACUCCCAGAGCUUCAUCCAGCAAUGUGUUCAGCAGACUUCUAGUGACAUGGUCAUUGCUACCUGUACUACAACAGUAACAACUUCUCCUGUGGUGACAACUACAGUGUCCUCAAGCCAGUCUGAAAAGUCAAUUAUUGUUUCUGGAGCAACAGCACCCAGAACUGUGUCAGUGCAAACUUUGAACCCACUUGCUGGUCCAGUGGGAGCAAAAGCUGGAGUUGUGACACUUCAUUCUGUGGGCCCAACUGCUGCAACAGGAGGAACAACAGCUGGAACUGGUUUGCUUCAGACUUCAAAACCACUUGUGACAUCUGUGGCAAACACAGUGACCACGGUCUCACUGCAACCUGAAAAGCCAGUUGUCUCUGGAACAGCAGUAACACUGUCCCUUCCAGCAGUAACUUUUGGAGAAACUUCAGGUGCAGCUAUUUGUCUUCCAUCUGUGAAACCUGUUGUUUCUUCUGCUGGGACCACAUCUGACAAGCCUGUUAUUGGGACUCCAGUUCAAAUCAAACUUGCCCAGCCGGGCCCUGUCCUUUCACAACCAGCUGGGAUUCCACAGGCAGUUCAAGUCAAGCAACUAGUAGUUCAGCAGCCUUCAGGAGGCAAUGAAAAACAAGUGACCACAAUUUCACAUUCCUCAACAUUGACCAUUCAGAAAUGUGGACAGAAGACGAUGCCAGUGAACACCAUAAUACCUACUAGUCAGUUUCCUCCAGCUUCCAUUCUAAAGCAAAUUACUCUGCCUGGAAAUAAAAUUCUGUCACUUCAAGCAUCUCCUACUCAGAAAAAUAGAAUAAAAGAGAAUGUAACAUCAUGCUUCCGGUCCUGUGAACCAAACAAUGGAAUGAAAAUGUCUUAUGCUGUGUAAUUGCUCCUCAGUAAAUCUAGUCCACUUACUGCCUGAAGGAAAAAUGUCACUAUAAGUAUUUUCUUUGGGAAAUUUCUGACUUAUUACUUUCGCCCAUUUAUCUGUUGACUACUUAUUGCUUUCCAGACUUAUGUACAUAUGCUGGACAGUAGUAAUUCUUUGAUAUAUACAUUGUAAGUAUUUUUCUCCUAGUUUUUUGUUUAACUUGGAAAUUUGUUUUUAGUGUUUCAUAUAUGGAAAAUUUAAAUUACAGUAUAAAGUUUAGCAGUCUCUUCCUUUAUGGCUUUUGAAUUCUAAUGUAUCCUUUCGUAUUAUGAGCCCAGAAUGAUGUGCCUUCUGUAUCUUCUUCUAAGAUACUUGUAUGCACUUACCUCAAAUACAGAUAUUUACCUUUAUAUCUUCAAUAAUUCUUGAUUUUAUUUUUGUAAAUGUGUGAGGCAGAGAUUAAAUUUUCCUCAAAUGAAUUGUCUGAGCAAUAGUUAGUAAAGAGUUCAUCAUCUUUAACUUUCUUAUUUGCAAUGCCACCUUUAUCUUAUAGUAAAUUCCCAUUUAAAAAAGGGCAAAUUUCAUUUUAGUGAUAUGUUUUUGUUUUAUUUUAUUUUAUUUUUUGAGAUACAGUUUCACUCUGUUGCCCAGGCUGGAGUGCAGUGGUGCGAUCUCAGCUCACCACAACCUCCACCUGCUGGGUUCAAACGAUUCUCGUGCCUCAGCCUCCCGAGUAGCUGAACUACAGGCACGCGCCACCACUCCCAGCUUAUUUUUGUAUUUUUAGUAGAGACGGGGUUUCAUCAUGUUGGCCAGGCCAGUCUCAAACUCCUGACCUCAGGUGAUCCACCUGCCUCGGCCUCCCAAAUAUUUGUUUUGUUUUGAUAUUACUAUUUUGGUGUUUUCGAUUGUUAUAACAUCUUUAUUUAUUUAUCUAGCCCAUAGUUAAAGUAAGUCCUUUUUCUAUAUUCCUUUUUAUCGAAGGUAUCUUAAUUUUACUUGUUAUUUUUCUCUCGUGCAUGAAUUUUAGAAUCAGCAUGGCAGUUCCAUGAAGUUUGUAUAGAAUUGUGUGAUUAGGUUAAUUUGGGUGGUGGGGGCAGAGAAUUGGCUUAAAGAAUUUUCUUUUUACGAUAUAGAAGAUUCCCAUCUGAAACCAUGGUUAUAUUUGUUAGAAUUUGGUAAGGUUGUAGGGAACAGAAAAACUGAAAAGCCAUUGCAUAAGCAAAUUAUCUCUCAUAUUCAGAAAAACUGAAUUGCAAGGAUCACGGUCUGUGGUGUUAGGGAUCCGUGCUCCAUGUUUGCCUCCUUUCUGUUCUUCGGACACACUAGUCAUGGUCCUGAUGUACAAUUUUAUUUAUUUAUUAUUUUCUUUAAUGUUUUUAAUGUUUAAUUUUGGGGGGUACAUAGGCGUAUAUUUAUGGGUUAUGUGAGAUUUUGAUAAAACCCACUGUAUAGUUUUUGAUGUGGUAUGCAGUGAAAGCUGUCCCUCAGUCUUCAUAUGACAUGGUCUUUCAUAUAUCAAAUCUACCUCCUUAGAGAGGUAAAUUUUGCUUGGCCAACCAACAUAAAGUAGCUUCCACAGUGAUAUCUGCUGUCUUGAGGUACUUAUCUAAAAUUAUUUUGUUCAUUUAUUUGUUUACCCCUGCUUCCAUGUAUUUCCCACUUCUUCUUAAUCGUCUAUGAAAGCUUACAAUGAUUGUUUACCAUUGUAUGUAUACCGAGUGUUUAGAACAAUGCCUGUUUCAUAAUAGGCAUUCAAAUAUUUGUUGAAAUGGUGAGUUUUGGAAAAGGAGUAUUUAUAAUCUCAGCUAUUUCUUAGAUAUUUUUGUACAAAGGUGCACUUUUCAUUUUUGUACAGUACUUUCUAGUAAUUCACAGUCACACAUGGCUUUAUGCAUAUCUUUUCAUAGUGAUGUCUUUUUAAAUUUAAUUUUGCUUCCCUGGAUACUUACAUCACUUCAGUUAUUUAUUUAUUUAUUUAUUUAUUUAUUUUUUAAGAUGGAGUCUCACUCUGUCUCCCAGGCUGGAGUGCAGUGCACGAUCUCGGCUCACUGCAAGCUCUGCCUCCUGGGUUCACGCCAUUCUCCUGCCUCAGCCUCCUGAGUAGCUGGGUCUACAGGCACCCGCCACCACACCCGGCUAAUUUUUUUUGUAUUUUUUUAGUAGUGACGGAGUUUCACCGUGUUAGCCAGGAUGGUCAGAUGGUCUCGAUCUCCUGACCUCGUGAUCCACCUGCCUCGGCCUCCCAAAGUGCUGGAAUUACAGGCAUGAGCCACCGUGCCCAGCCUUACUUCAGUUACUUUUUAAAUGAAACUGAUAAUAGACCCUCGAUGUUGGCUCUUUUGUUAAAUAAGAAGAAAUAGUAGCGAAUAAUAUUAGCUCUUGUCUUGACCAAACUGUAUGACAUUUAAUAAUAUAGAAUGAUAUUUUCAUAGUUUUUAAAAACUAUUUUGUUAACUUACACUUUUCGGGGGGAUUCAUUUGUGACUUUUUCUGCUAAGAAGAUUCUGUUUUCUAUUCUGCUUGUCAGUAUAGCUGGGGUGAAUUUGGGAAGCUGUAUUGUGCUUAAACACCAGAGGGUGCCAGAGAUUCAUGUUCUUUCCAUCAUACUUCAGAAUCAGAAGUGGCAAACAGGAUAGUACCUCUGCAUGUUUGCAUAACCGUAUUUCAACUGAAGAUGUGAUGAUAAUAAGGAAUUAAUAUCAAUAUUUUUAUGUGAUCAUUUAUUUAAAGUCCUUAUAUUUUAGAGAUACAUAAUAAAAUAUUUAUGGAUAAUAUCUAUAUACUAUAUCUGGUAGUGAAGGUGUUUUAACAACUAGGGGUUUUAGUGUGAUUUUUAUUACUUUAAAAAGACACUCUUGGAAAAUAAUAUAGGACCAGAUUAUGUGCUGUUUGCAUAGAUGGUAUUACUCCAUCAAUUUUAAUGUCCAUUUUUUCCAUACUGCAGGAAUUAGAUUGUCUAGUGUAUAUUAACUUAUUUAACUUUCAUCAUAUAUAAUUCAUUGUUUUAUGUAUUACGAGUCUGUUUGUCCUUGUGUAUGCUCACGCUUGUAAUCCCAGCACUCUGGGAGGCUGAGUUGGGAAGAUCACCUGAGGUCAGGAGUUCGAGACCAGCCUGACCAACGUGGCGAAACUCCAUCUCCACUAAAAAUACAAAAAUGAGCCGGGUGUGGUGGUGCGCCUGUAGUCCCAGCUACUUGGGAGGCUGAGGCAGGGAGAAUUGCUUGAACCUGGGAGGCAGAGGUUGCAGUGAGCCGAGAUGGAGCCAUUGCACUCAAGCCAAAAACAAAAAACCCCCCAAAAUUAGUUGGGCAUGGUGGCGCACGCCUGUAAUCCUAGCUACUUGGGAGGCUGAGGCGGGAGAAUGACCUGAGCUCCGGAAGUGAAGGCUGCAGAAAGGUGAGAUUGCACCGCUGCACUCCAGCCUGGGUGUCUUAAUAAAAAAGAGAGAGAGAAAAAA